ACCGCCGUCCCCACCGCCAUCCGCCCUCCCGGCCUGGCCUGCCCUUGCGCCCGGCUCCCCAGUGCCCGCCGCCCGCCCGCCGCGCUCCCGCGCUCCGUUCCGCCCAGGCCGCGCCCAGCUGGAAUGCAGAGAUCGCCGCCCGGCUACGGCGCACAGGACGACCCGCCCGCCCGCCGCGACUGUGCAUGGGCCCCGGGACACGGGGCCGCCGCUGACACGCGCGGCCUCGCCGCCGGCCCCGCCGCCCUCGCCGCGCCCGCCGCGCCCGCCUCGCCGCCCAGCCCGCAGCGCAGUCCCCCGCGCAGCCCCGAGCCGGGGCGCUAUGGCCUCAGCCCGGCCGGCCGCGGGGAACGCCAGGCGGCAGACGAGUCGCGCAUCCGGCGGCCCAUGAACGCCUUCAUGGUGUGGGCAAAGGACGAGCGCAAGCGGCUGGCUCAGCAGAACCCGGACCUGCACAACGCGGUGCUCAGCAAGAUGCUGGGCAAAGCGUGGAAGGAGCUGAACGCGGCGGAGAAGCGGCCCUUCGUGGAGGAAGCCGAACGGCUGCGCGUGCAGCACUUGCGCGACCACCCCAACUACAAGUACCGGCCGCGCCGCAAGAAGCAGGCGCGCAAGGCCCGGCGGCUGGAGCCCGGCCUCCUGCUCCCGGGAUUAGCGCCCCCGCAGCCACCGCCCGAGCCUUUCCCCGCGGCGUCUGGCUCGGCUCGCGCCUUCCGCGAGCUGCCCCCGCUGGGCGCCGAGUUCGACGGCCUGGGGCUGCCCACGCCCGAGCGCUCGCCUCUGGACGGCCUGGAGCCCGGCGAGGCUGCCUUCUUCCCACCGCCCGCGGCGCCCGAGGACUGCGCGCUGCGGCCCUUCCGCGCGCCCUACGCGCCCACCGAGUUGUCGCGGGACCCCGGCGGUUGCUACGGGGCUCCCCUGGCGGAGGCGCUCAGGACCGCGCCCCCCGCGGCGCCGCUCGCUGGCCUGUACUACGGCACCCUGGGCACGCCCGGCCCGUACCCCGGCCCGCUGUCGCCGCCGCCCGAGGCCCCGCCGCUGGAGAGCGCCGAGCCGCUGGGGCCCGCCGCCGAUCUGUGGGCCGACGUGGACCUCACCGAGUUCGACCAGUACCUCAACUGCAGCCGGACUCGGCCCGACGCCCCCGGGCUCCCGUACCACGUGGCACUGGCCAAACUGGGCCCGCGCGCCAUGUCCUGCCCAGAGGAGAGCAGCCUGAUCUCCGCGCUGUCGGACGCCAGCAGCGCGGUCUAUUACAGCGCGUGCAUCUCCGGCUAGGCCGCCGGCGCCGCCCGGGUCCCUGCAGCGCUUCCUCCCGCAGCCCCCGCGACCGAUCCGACCGCGUCGCUGCCGCUCUGCUCUCUCAUACGCGUGUAUGUUUGGUUCCAUGUCACAGCCCCCUAGGAGCCAGUGAUGCUCGGCCUUGCGCCCGUUCCACCUCCCAGGCCACCCUUCCUGGGCUUCUGGGCCACCUGCCCUCGGGGGGCCCCUGCGAGGGUGCCUGGAGUUCCCACGUGUCCCGGGGCUUUUCCAGGAAGCCCGAGCCCAGGACCUGUUGGCAGAGUUGCCAGGGUUACAUUUUUGAAGCACCUGCUCCUUUUCUUGCAGUGUAUUUUCUACAACCAGAUUGUAUUAAUAUUUUUUACUUUGCCCUUUUAAAAAAUAUACCUAAUACAAUAUAUUUAAUUUUUAAUUAAACUCUUAAACUUUUCUUCCAAGAAGUUUCAGUGAUCAGAAGCGUCACUGUGGCAAAGACUUUUGCAAUGUGAGGAAUACAGAUGUUUGCUUUCUAUAAAGGAGGAGCCUGGAGCUGGGUCCCCGGACGGAGAGGCCACAAUAAAUCCUCGGGCCUUUCCUCUGCA